AUGGAGGAUUCUCGUGGAGUAGGUGUCUUUCCAAGAAGAGAGCCCACUCAGCCACCGCCCUCUGCAGCAACAGCAGCAGCAGGCUACUGCUCCUGCAGGUCCUUCUACAGGGGCCUCGGGAACCAGCCCCAGUUCCUGGGGAUGCAGAUCCUGAGAGUCAGCUUCAUCUGCUUUGGGCGCAGGGCCUUGCCCAUUGUCAAGUUGGCAGAUGAGAGGAGCCAAUGCAAAGGGCACAUUGAAGUCUACCACAAUGGCACAUGGGGGACUGUGUGCGACAACCUCUGGGGCGUCAACGCUGCCCACAUGGUGUGCCAGCAGCUGGGUUUUCCUGCUUCAAUUUCAGCCACAGAUUUUGCCCUUACACCUGAGCCGCCCCUGCGCCUGGCGGGCGGGCGGAGCCGCUGUGAGGGCCGGGUAGAGCUGCGGCACCAGGGCGUGUGGGGCACGGUGUGCGACGACCACUGGAACAUCAGGAACGCCCGUGUGGUGUGCCGCCUCCUGGGUUGCGGCCGUGCUCUGGGCGCCCCGGGCCGCGGCCGCUUUGGCCAGGGCACCGGGCCCAUCCUGCUGGACGACGUGCGCUGCACCGGCCACGAGAACGCGCUGGAGCGCUGCACCCACUCGGGCUGGGCCCGGCACAACUGCCAGCACCGCGAGGACGCGGGCGUGGUGUGCGCAGGUCUGGCUGACUCUCUUGUACCUAAGGACAAUGCCCAGCUAUCCUGCUUGCCUCACCUCUUCCAAGCCGUCAUUGACCGAGGCUAUCUCCGGAGGCUGGGCUACUCCUCCUGGGACAUCCACUUAAAUGAUGAGCUAUGUCGCCCCAAAGUCAUGGGACGCUGCCUGAUCUUCAACAUUCCCUAUGGCCACUGUGGCACUAUCCAGCAGGAGCACCUUGGCUCCCUCAGCUACUCUAACUCCAUCAGAGGCCGGAAACGGGGCCACCCUGGCCGAGUCAUUGUGCGGCACAAGGUGCCCAAGCUGAAGUUCACCUGUAGGGCGGACGGCCCAUCCACAGUUGAAAUCAUUCAUGGGGAUGACGCCCCAACAGAGGGUGCUGGCUACACCGUGUCUAUAUCCUUCCUCCAGUCCCCUGAGUCCCAGCAUGUGGGAGGCAUGGUGCCCUACUAUGACAGCCAGAGGAAAGAGGUCUUCCUCCAAGCCACCCUCCACAGCCCCAAUCCCAACCUGAUGCUCUUCGUGGAUACCUGUGUGGCUUCUCCUGAUCCCCAUGAUUUUACAGCCAUCAAGUAUGAUUUGAUCCGGCAGGGGUGCAUCAAAGACAAUACCUACAUCAACCUCCAUCCCCGCCAGAAGAACAUGGCUCAGUUCAAGUUCAAUGUCUUCAGCUUUCUUGACAGCUAUGAUGUGGUAUAUCUGCAGUGUAAGGUUGCAGUGUGCAAGGUGGGGGAUUAUGCCUCUCUCUGCUCCUGGGGCUGUACAGGACAGAGUAGGAGAGGUGCAGGCCCCAUGGAGGCCAAGGAAAAGCAGACUGAGCAUUUCCAAAUGGUGGGGCCACUGGAGAUCCACAAAGUCACUGCUCAGAGGAGGACUCUUGAGUGAUUUCUGCAAUUUUCAUGUAAAUCUGUAGAAAGCAAAGUCUAUUUCUCUUCAGUAAUGUUUGACCAAUCAGACGCUAUCCGCAUAGAGACAGGUCAAAGAAACAGCCAGAGGGGAUUGCUUCUCUGAGGUUUGUUACUAAACAAAUCUUCUCUGAUUACUAAACUUCUAAGGCAAUUACUCUCUUUGCUGCCACAAAUGCUACAUUUUCUAAUUCUUGUCUUAAAGUGUACAAAAUGUUACAAAGAGCAGGGUUAUCUCUCUAUACCGCAUUGUCAAUUUAAAGAUUGUCUUUUUAAGUUGACUGUUUAAUCAUCAGAUGCUAUUAAGUGGAUCUCUGUUUUUAUCCUCUGACGGUACGAGGAUUUAUUUUCAACUCUUGCCAAGAGUCUUAGGUAAAAUAAAAUAAGUGUCUGUCACUCA